UGCUUUUCGGCCAACCGAGAAAUGUAGAGUAUUUGGGGGCGUUUCUCACAGGUGGGCAGACUGUUAGGAUGGCGAGGGCCCAGUGUGGGUGCUUUGGUUCUCUCCAGAAGGUUGAUGUCUGGACCGAGAAGGUACCCGAGUGUUCUCCACCGCUUCCUAAAAUCUGACACCGUGUGGCCUUGGGGUGCAGGUGCUGGGUGUCCCCACAGCCACCCUCAAGACCGUAUCCUGAGGCAGCAAUUUGACAAAGCCUGCACCUCUGGCUUGGGCCCACACCUAUCUCUAAGGACUGAUUAGGGGGCUUUUCUUGUUUUUUUUUUUUUUUUUUUUUUAGAGCCAGAGUCUCGCUUUGUCGCCCAGGCUGGAGUGCAAUGGCUGAUCUCGGCUCACUGUAAUCUCCGCCUCCCUGGUUCAAGCGAUUCUCGUGCCUCAGCCCCUGGAGUAGCUGGAACUACAGACGUGGGCUCCCACGCCCAGCUAAUUUAUGUGUUUUUAGUAGAGAUGGGGUUUCGCCAUGUUGGCCAGGCUGGUCUCGAACUCCUGGCCUCAAGUGAUCCACCUGCCUCCACCUCCCAGAGUGCUGGGAUUACAGGUGUGAGCCACUAUCCCCGACCCAGGGGGCUUUUCAAGAAUGAUUCAUCUCGCAUAAUGUUUUAAAGCCACAAGCUGUCCUGGGGAGACGACCCCCCUCGAUUUUUUUUUUUCUUUCUGAGAUGGAGUCUCGUUCUGUCUCCUAGGCUGGAGUGCAGUGGCGCGAUCUCGGCUCACUGCAACCUCUGCCUCCUGGGUUCAAGCAAUUCUCCUGUCUCAGCCUCCCCAGUAGCUGGGAUUACGGGCACACGCCACCACGCCCAGCUAAUUUUUGUAUUUUUAGCAGAGGAGGGGUUUCACCAUAUUGGCCAGGCUGGUCUCAAACUCCUGACCUCAGGUGAUCCACCUGCCUCAGCCUCCCAAAGUGCUGGGAUUACAGGCGUCAGCCACUGCACCUGGCCAGAUUUUUUAAUACCAUUCUUGAACUAGGUGAUUUGACAACUUAGAAAACUGUUCACUGGGUGUCCAGGCCUUCUCUGCAACCAGUCAGAAGCUGUAAAUGUGGCUAGUGGAGAACAGACUAUUUCCCCAGGAAAACUCCCCUCCCCGACCUUGUCAUCUAGUGUAAAGACACUGACUUGGGCCGGUUUUCUUAAGGUAGUAUUUAAGGUAGUAUUCUUAAGGUAGUAUUGCUGUUUAAGGAGUCAAUAGUCUUAAUUUAGACGCUCCUCAGCCCAAGGCUAAUGCAAAUGUUUUGUCAUUUAUGUCAUUUUGCAGAGGCAAUUUGAAUAACACCUACAGUAAGGCAGGCGUGGGUUUGCUAGCCAGUGAAAGAGCUCCUCUCGCAUUGUUGGUCCCCCAGUGCUCUGUGUCAGUGGGGAAUCUCUCCAGAAGUCAAAAGUCUAUUGAAAAAGCAGAGAGAGAAUGCCUCGGUGUGUAAGUGGAGUGAUGAGGACCUGAUCUCUGGGCCGUGUGGGAACACUGGCUGCCAUUUCAUCACAGUCAACCUGGACUCACAGAAUUUCAAGAAGGAAGCGCCUGGUUAACCGGAGAAAGCUCCUGGUAAAGAAGAAUCCAUAACAGAGGCAAAACAUACUGGCCAGUUUUCGCCCACUGCUGAGGUCCUGAGGGCAGCCACAGCCUCUGAGCCAAGGGGAGUUCAGUGUCCAUAAGCCUUGGAGGCUUGCUUGCACAAGAACCGCUUUGCACUGCAAUUUUGGGGUAGGCAGGAGCUUGUCGGUUGGGUCAAGAAUGAACCUACGCAUGACGGCGUGCUGAUCCUGGGUUUCUAGUCAUCCUUUUUAAGCUGCAAAGAAGCAUUUGCAGACGUUGUCUCAUGGGUACCGCUUGCCAACUUUGGAGGAUGUGAAGCCGGUAGAGAAAUAAAGCAUCGCCCCUCUGCGCGCCCCUCCCCGUCUGCUAGAAUGUUUCUCAUGAACGCUUCUCCAGUGGUUGCUCUCCAGUCCAAAUGGGAGGCCUUUGGCCCGCCAGGGAGCUGUAGGUUCCCCAGGUGCUUCUCGGAGGCUGACGAGGGCGUGGAGAGCGCGUCGGUGAGCGCCCGGGUGCAGAUGCUUAUCAGCACUCUGCAGCGCGACGGGGCUGCUCGGGGCACCAGCGAUGAGCGCGCCGCACAGAGGGGCCACAGGGCAGAGGGAUGCCACGACGCCAGGCCGGCUGCCAAGCCCACCGUGCACAAGGAGCCACCCGCGUUGGCUGUCUGUGGUCUCGUUGCUGACUUUGACCCCAUGGGGGAGGAGGAAACUACAGACUUUGGCCCGUUGGUGCUAGAUUCAGACAGUGAUGAUUCCGUGGACAGGGACAUUGAGGAGGCCAUCCAGGAGUACCUGAAGGCAAAGAGUGGAGCCGCACAGCCCGGGGCCGGCGGGGCCCAGCCAGGUGCAGCCCAGCCUUCCAGGGCCGCAGGCGGAGGCAGUAGAUGUAAGCCGGAACCGGCUCACGGCAGUGCCCCGACUGCCCUGUGUCCCCCAAAACUUGUACCUGGAUCAGGUGGUGGCCCCGGCAGCCAGGUGGGAUCCAGCAAGGACCAGGGCUCCGCCUCCCCGGUCAGUGUGAGCAGCGAUGACUCCUUCGAGCAGAGCAUCAGGGCGGAAAUAGAACAGUUUCUGAAUGAGAAGAGACAGCAUGAGACCCAAAAAUGUGAUGGGUCAGUGGAGAAGAAACCAGACACAAAUGAAAAUUCCGCCAAGUCACUCUUGAAAUCCCACCAAGAGCCGCCUACAAAGGUGGUGCAUCGGCAGGGCCUGCUGGGCGUCCAGAAGGAGUUUGCCUUCCGCAAACCUCCCCGGUUAGCGAAGAUGAACGUCCAGCCCAGAAGCCUCAGGUCCAAGGUCACAACCACGCAGGAGAACGAGGGCAGCACGAAGCCGGCAACCCCCUGCCGCCCUUCAGAAGCAGCACAGAAUAAAGGUGGGAUCAAAAGGAGCGCCAGCGCUGCAAGGAGGGGAAAGCGAGUCAUGAGUGCGGCACAGGCGUCCGAGGCGUCCGACUCCAGCAGCGACGAUGGCAUUGAGGAGGCCAUCCAGCUGUACCAGCUGCAGAAAACACGCAAGGAGGCCGACGGGGACCUGCCCCAGAGGGUCCAACUCCGAGAGGAGAGAGCGCCUGACCCUCCCGCACACAGCACAAGCAGUGCCACAAAAAGUGCCUUGCCCGAGACCCACAGGAAAACACCCAGCAAGAAGAAGCUAGUGGCCACCAAGACCAUGGACCCUGGUCCAGGGGGCCUGGACACUGACCAUGCCCCCAAGCUCCUGAAGGAAACCAAAGCUCCACCUCCAGCGAGCCCUGCUUCCAGGAGUGAGUUUGUGGAACGGUCCUCGUGCCGGGCGGACACAUCUGCUGAGCUGAUGUGUGCAGAAGCAAUCCUGGACAUCUCCAAGACGAUCCUGCCGGCCCCUGUAGAGGGCAGUGACGGGUCCCUGUCCGCAAGCCCACUCUUCUACUCCCCGAACGUGCCUUCCCGCUCUGACGGCGACAGUAGCUCCGUGGACAGCGAUGACAGCAUCGAGCAGGAAAUCCGGACAUUUUUGGCCCUAAAGGCGCAGUCAGGGAGUUUGCUGGCCAGAGGUGAGAGCUGCCCGCAGGCUGCCCAGGGUCCACUUUUGCCGCCUGGCCUCAACAGCCAGACCGGCGGCCACAAGACCCCUCUCUCUAAAACACCAGACCCACUGCUGGGCUGCAAAAGGAAGCGUAGAGGUGGUGGCCAUGUGAGGCCAUCCACGCCCAAGAAAAUGCAGGAGGUGGUGAAAGACGGUAGCCAGGAUGCCGACCACAGCCAGGGGAGAGCUGAGCCCGGCCAUGAGAGGCGAGACCUGCCCAUCCAGGGCAAAGCCAGUGAGGCCCUGGGAGGGGAGGGCACCGCCAGGGGCCCUGGCGACACUCGCAUGUCACAGGGCCAGGGUAAGACAGACGAGGCAAGGCGCCUAGACGAGAAAGAGAGCUCUGAAGACAAAAGCAGCUCCCUGGACAGUGACGAGGACCUGGACACAGCCAUCAAGGACUUGUUAAGGUCCAAGCGAAAGCUCAAGAAGAGGUGCAGGGAGCCCAGGGCUGCGUGCAGGAAGAAGGUCAGGUUCAGCACAGCCCAGACGCACUUCUUGGAGCAGCUGGGCGGGCUCCGGAGAGACUGGAAAGACAGGGGCCCGCCAGUGCUGAAGAGCUGCCUCUCCAAGUCCAAGAGAGACAGUGGCGAGGGUCCUGGGAAGAAACCCCCCAGUGUCUUUGGCAGCACGGCAGAGAGGAUGAGGCAGGAGGGUGCCGCGAGCCAGGACGCGGCCCUGGCCUUCCGGGUGAGGAGACCCGCCUCCGCCUCUGCCUCCGAAGGGAAUCCAUUCCCCAGGGAGUCCCAGGGCCCAGCUCCCAGCCCCGGCUCCCUGUCUGAUGACAGCAGUUCAGUGGACAGCAACGACAGCAUCGAACUGGAGAUUAGGAAGUUUUUGGCGGAAAAGGCCAAGGAGUCAGUGAGCAGUUCAGAAGUUCAGGCAGAGGGCCCCACCGCUCUUGGGACAGGGGGCCCAGCCAGGCCAGAGGUGCUGUGCAGGAAGGAGCCUGCCCCACCGCCUGGCGUGUGCACACGCAGCCAGAGGGCCAGGGGGGUCCCACAUCUGGCCGAAGGGCUUCGAGGCACAGAGAGCGCAGGAGCACAGGGCACAGCUGGUCUGUUCAGCCAGGGCGGGAAGGGGCUCCCUGCUGCUCCUGCCCGAGGGGAUCCGGUGCCGCCCAGGAGCACCAGCGGCGGUGUCUCCGCCAAGGGGCUCUCAGUGAGCAGGAGAAAUGUUUACGUUCACAAAGACCAGAGCCCACGAGGGGCUGAGCCUGCUGCCAAAAGUGCUUUUGGUCAGCUGCCCAGCUGUGCCACAGCGGGCACCGAGGCAGGAGGCGCCAGAGGAACCUUUCACAUGGGCUGCGGGAGCCCGAGCUUCCUGACCCCCAGCCCGGGAGCGGAGAGGGACGCUGGAGCCCAGGCCGACCGCACACCGCCCUGGAGCGACUUCGCCCACCAGAGUCGGCUGCCCAGCCCGUGGGUGCUGCGCUCCGAAGGCAGAGAUGCAGUGUGGAGGGGGGGCGUCGGGAGCGAGAGAGACAAGGGGUCCGAGGGCCCCGCCCGGGGCCUGCCCAGCCUGCCCCUUGCGGGCUUCUCGCCGCUGCUGUCCACCCAGCUCUUCCACUUUGGAAAGGGUGUCUCCUGGGGGGGCAGGCAGGCUGGCCUCUUCAGCCCCCACCUGGGGCUGCCUCUGCAGGGCCCCUCCUUCUCGGCCUUCAGGGAGGCCCAGGCCGGACCCAGCCCUGUCUUUGGAAGCCCACACUUGCUGGCAAAGAAGGACGGCGGCCCCUGGCCAACCAGGAAGGCACAGGCAGGGCUGAGUUUGCAUGACAGGAGGAGCUCGGGCUCGGAGGAAAGCAUUUUAGACCUGAGGUAUCGACGAAGGGUCAACAGGGAUGACCAGGAGCAGGACGCCUUGGGCAGUGACGCCAGUGACUUCAGCGACACCUCCACGGAGGACAGUGGCGGCAGCUCAGUAGUGAAGGUCUAAGCCCUCGAGCUGUGGGUUCGCGUCCUGGGUUGCGUGCAUUCGUGGAAAGCGGCGUAGCCGUGCGUGUGUGUGAUGGUUCCGUGGCUGCAAGGAAGGGAAACAGUCUAUUAUACAUAGCCCUGUAUAUAUGUACACCAACAUGAAACUUUUAUUUAACAGACGUGUCCUGGUAAAUAUGAUUUUUGUAGCUUUUUGUAAAUUAUUUAAAGUGAUGUAAAAGAUAUUUUUGGAAAAUACUGUUGUUCAAUUUUGUAGGGUGUUCCUAACUGCAGUUUUCUGUGUUCUGCAUACAAGUCUUAGCUUAGGAAACAUUUGGUUCUUACCAUCACAGCCAGGUUCACAGAGGCUCUGAUGCUUUUUGGUUGAUUGCUGGUGAGAAUGGCCGGCGGUGGCUGCAGUGGUAGCCUGAGGAAGGCCAAGCUGCCCUCCCUGGGAAUCACUCAGAUGCCCCAAGAUGUCCGUUGGGAAGCUCCCAGGACAGCACUUUUUAUACAGAGGACACCGCCUCGGCCCCACGUCCUUAGAGGCCAGAGCACAUCUGAAAACUGCAAUCACAGCCGUCCGCUGGAAAAACGUUUCGAAGCACAGUGGCCAGCGAGCGAGCACGUGGCUACUCCCUGUUGCAUGUCAAAUCCACACAGAUGUCAGCGGCAGCUGCUCGGCAGCCCAGCCCUGGGCCUGGGUGGGUUCAUGUCCAAUCUUGUUCGAUCACUAGAUGAUUCUAACAUCGAAAUAAACCUCUUUUUAUAUGG